GCAUGGUGACUCACAUCUGUAGUCCCAGCUACUCUGGAGGCUGAGGUGGGAGGAUCACCUGAACCCUGGAAGUCCAGGAUGCAGUUAGCUGUGAUCGCACCACUGGACUCCAGCCUGGACAAUGGGAGUGAGACCUUGUCUCAAAAAAAAAAAAAAAAAAAAAGUAUUUUGUAACCUGCUAGCUAGGACUGGCCUUAGUUGCUGCUGCUCUUGAUUCUUAUGAGAUGCAGAAAACCAAGGUCAAGAGAGUAGGUGAUGACACCAUUUUACCCCUGCUUGGGAGCAGGUCCAUCAAUCAAAUGGUAGUAGCCCAGGUUUUUAGACACACAUCAAAUCCUCUUCUGCCAGGCCCACCUGCCAGCCCUCCUCACUGUUUCUGCACAGUUCUAAAAGGAUGGUUCAGUUCCCUCACCCUGCCUAACCCAAGGCAAGUUUCCUCUUCACUAAGUCCAUUCUGGUCCCACUAUCCCCUAAAUUCUUCUAGCAGGUCCCUACAGCCAUUAAACUCAUUCUUUUGGAUAAAGGCAAAGGUGGCCAUCCAGUAGAGAAGGGCCCCCAGGCAGGUCUCAGUGUUCCCCAGAAGUCAAAACUCAGACUGCCUUAUUGCUGCACAUCACUUCACCACGCACAAAGCACUUUCUCAGGCCACAUCCCAUUUAACCCCCAAAGGGAGGCAGGAUGGUAGCAUCCUGCUGGGGAUACUUUGGAACCUGCUGGGGCAGUUGGAACUUGGGGAGGGAGGAUGGGCUGAUAGCUUCAGCCAGAGAUUGGGAGGCUGGAGGCAGGGCAUGAGGGGAUGUAACUCCCCUUGAUUUCCUUCUGUAAAAUGGGAAUGAUACCACUUCACGCACUUGCUAUGCAUGUGCAUUCAUUAUGGCUCUCAAACUGAGUGUGGGAGAAGGGGGUACAGGAUGGUGCUGCUGAAUAUACAUGGCACAUACAUCAUCUUCCUGGAAUUUUACUUGAGGGUUUGGAGGUGGUGAGUUUUAUAAUAAAACUUGGAUUUAUUAUGCAGCAGAAUGCAAACCUGGUGUGUAUUUAAAGAUUUUAAAAGGAGUUUUGAAAGUGAUGUCAUGCUUCUAGUGGGCUGCUUCUGGCUACACCCCCAGAUCCCUGGGGAUUGGGCACGUGAUCACACCCUAGUGUGCCAUGUAAGGGCUUCAGUAGGAAAGUGGGAGCAAUGCUGCCUGAUGGAAGAUGAGAAAGUGCCUGACAUGCAAUAGGCAGGUAGCAUUUGAUGGUUCGUGUUACGGCAGCAGCUAUGUCCUCCCAGGGGAAACAGGCCCACACAGAUGGCAGUACUUGGUUGGGUUCACUCAGCUGGAAGGUGACACAGCCAUGACUGGAACCAACUACUGACUUCCCACCCAGUGCUCUACCAUAACUUCCAUCUCCUCCCCAUGGGAAAGGGCUUUAUGGUCAGCAGCCCUCUUCUACUUAGGCCACCUCCUCAGUUCUCUCUCUCCCUCUUAGAACUCCCUCUUGUCAGGGAGGUGUAUUCCUCUGGGGGUACAACAUGUGUAACUGUGCUAAAAGGCAAGUGCCUCUGUGGGGAGGCGGCAGACACAGUUGACAUGAGCCAACCUGUGUACUUCAGAGAGGACACAGGGCUGCCGAGUUGCGGGUGGUAAGAGGAGAGGUCCAGAGGAUGGGAUGCUCUCAAGAUUAGCUGGAGGCUAGAAGAGAUAAGGGGCACACCAAAAAAACAAAAACAAAAAACAAAAAACAAAAAACAACCCUCGUCUCCUUCCCAGGUUUGUCUAAGUUGACAGGCCCUCAGGUUUGCACCUUAUUUUCUUUCUUUUUCUUUUUUUUGAGACGGAGUCUCACUCUGCUGCCAGGCUAGAGUGCAGUGGCUCGAUCACAGCUCACUGCAACCUCCACCUCCCAGAUUCAAGCGAUUCUCCUGCCUCAGCCUCCCAAGUAGCUGGGACCACAGGCGCAUGCCACCAUGUCCGGCUAAUUUUUGUAUUUUUAGUAGAGACGGGGUUUCACCAUGUUGGCUAGGAUGGUCUUGAUCUCUUGACCUUGUGAUCCGCCCACCUCAGUCUCCCAAAGUGCUGGGAUUACAGGCAUGAGCCACCUCGCCCAGCCCGGCAUCUUAUUUUCAUGGCUUAAGAUUUCUAGGUCCAGAUAAAAACCAAGGGUGCCCUGGGCCUUGCCAGCUAAUGAGUGCAUAGAAUCCAGGGAUAGCAAGAGAGGCUUGGAGAGCCUUUUCUUUCUCCAGCCCUGUUCUUUCUCCAGGCCCUGCCAGGCUGGCCUUCCUGCCCUGGGCCUGUGUACAGGUUUGUUUCUGUGUAUGUCUGUCUCCCUAAAUGAGAGGAACCAAGGUCCUGAGUGAAGGAAUCAGUGAUUGAGAUUUGUUCAGCUUCUGCCUCAUACCAUGGAAUGGGAUGGGGGAGCUGGGCGCCUAUCAUGCUUAAGCCUUAUGUACUACUCACAGCAACCCAGUAAGGAUAGUUAUUUCCUCAUUUUAUAGAUCUUUUUCUUACAGAUGCACAGAGGCUUGUUUCUUGGGCCCUGGAAUCUUUUGAGGCAUUGGUAGUAAUAAAAAUUUGGGGGGCCGGGCCUGGUGGCUCACACCUGUAAUCCCAGCAGUUUGGGAGGCUGAGGUGGGUGGAACACCUGAGAUCAGGAGUUGGAGACCAGCCUGACCAAUAUGGUGAAACCCUGUCUCUACUAAAAAUACAAAAAAUUAGCCGGGCAUAGUGGUGUGCACCUGUAGUCUCAGCUACUCGGGAGGCUGAAACAAGAGAACCGCCUGAACCCGGGAGGUAGAGGUUGCAGUGAGGCCAGAUCGCGCCACUGCACUCCAGCCUGGGUGACAGAGCAAGACUCCAUCUGAAAAAAAAAAAAAAAAAAAAAAAAAAUGGCCCUACUCUAGACCAACUUAGAACAUCCCUGCGGUAGGCCUGAUAAUCUGCAAUUUUUAACAAGGGUGACCAUCAGGUAAUUCCGAUGUUCACAACAGUUCAAAAACCUCGACAGAGCAUUUUCGUAACCUGCCCACGCGUUCUUCAGUGGCAGAGCUGGAGCGCAAACCGGGGGCUUCAGAUGCUAAGUCCAGGCUCUUGACAGCUCACUGGAGACGCUGGAAUCACCUUCACUGCGCCUGUAUCAGCACCCGCCACACAGGCGCACAAAUAAACCUUCCCAGAGUGAAUGAAUGAAUUAAUGACUCAUCCAGCCCCAGCUGCUUCCGAAAAACCACUGGCAGAAGAUCCGGACCAUGGUCAAUCUGCCGGUCAUAAGCCCUUUCAAGAAGCGCUACGCCUGGGUGCAGCUGGCAGGGCACACUGGGAGUUUUAAGGCGGCGGGCACCAGCGGGCUGAUCCUGAAGCGCUGCUCGGAGCCGGAGCGCUACUGCCUGGCGCGGCUGAUGGCUGACGCGCUGCGCGGCUGCGUGCCUGCCUUCCACGGCGUGGUGGAGCGCGACGGCGAAAGCUACCUGCAGCUGCAGGACCUGCUCGAUGGCUUCGACGGACCUUGUGUGCUCGACUGCAAAAUGGGCGUCAGGACUUACCUAGAGGAGGAGCUGACCAAGGCCCGUGAGCGGCCCAAGCUGCGGAAGGACAUGUACAAGAAAAUGCUGGCGGUGGAUCCUGAAGCUCCCACGGAGGAGGAGCACGCGCAGCGCGCCGUCACCAAGCCGCGCUACAUGCAGUGGCGGGAAGGCAUCAGCUCCAGCACCACCCUCGGCUUCCGCAUCGAGGGCAUCAAGAAAGCGGACGGCUCCUGCAGCACCGACUUCAAGACUACGCGAAGCCGAGAGCAGGUGCUUCGCGUCUUUGAAGAGUUUGUGCAAGGAGAUGAGGAAGUGCUGAGGCGGUAUCUGAACCGCCUGCAGCAGAUCCGGGACACCCUGGAGGUAUCCGAGUUCUUCAGGAGGCACGAGGUGAUCGGCAGCUCGCUCCUCUUUGUGCACGAUCACUGCCAUCGCGCCGGCGUGUGGCUCAUCGACUUCGGCAAGACCACGCCCCUCCCCGAUGGCCAGAUCCUGGACCACCGGCGGCCCUGGGAGGAGGGCAACCGCGAGGACGGCUAUUUGCUGGGGCUGGACAAUCUCAUUGGCAUCCUGGCCAGCCUGGCUGAGAGAUGAGGCUGGACUCCUGUCCCCGCGGGCCGCUCACCUGACAUGUGGACCUGCAGCUUUGUCCCCACUGUGCAUGCCGGCUUGAGACUGGAGCCCCGCGGUGCAGGGCAGUUCACCGGGUCCUGCAGGACCAGGUGCCAGCCACUAAGGGGGGGCACCGCCGAUGCCAGGGGUUUUGCCCACCCGGGCCCCAGCGUUCCCAGAGCCAAAUGACACUAACUUAUAGAAGGGGAGGGGGCAAAGGGCUUCUUCCUCAGGCCAGCUCUUCUGAGGAGGCUCUGCCCUCUCCAGAGGUGCCAGACCGCGGAUUUUAUUUAGCAAGCCCAGACCUUCCGGUCUAACGUCUCACACCACGACGGACUCCCCUUCCUAAUAAAACUCAAAGACAAGA